AAACACAAAAUGAUUUUAUAGAGUAUGCAUAUAGCAUUUACAGCCAUAAGAGUACAUGAAGUCCAAGAGGAAGUAUGUGUGUAAAUAACGAAGAGGUACAAGGACAGAAGCCUUGGAAACAUCAACAGGUCUGGAAGAAAGGGAGGAACCAGAAAAAAAGACUGGAGAGGAGCCAACCUCCCCCUGCUCCCCUUCCCCCUGACUCUAUGAGUUCAGAGAAGCCGAACUGGGAUUACCAUGCAGAAAUACAAGCUUUUGGACAUCGGUUACAGGAAAACUUUUCCUUAGAUCUUCUCAAAACUGCAUUUGUUAAUAGCUGCUAUAUUAAAAGUGAGGAGGCCAAACGCCAACAACUUGGGAUAGAGAAAGAAGCUGUUCUUCUGAAUCUUAAAAGUAAUCAAGAACUAUCCGAACAAGGGACAUCUUUUUCACAGACUUGCCUUACACAGUUUCUUGAAGACGAGUACCCAGACAUGCCCACUGAAGGCAUAAAAAAUCUUGUUGACUUUCUCACUGGUGAGGAAGUCGUGUGUCACGUGGCUAGAAACUUGGCUGUGGAGCAGUUAACACUGAGUGAAGAAUUCCCAGUGCCCCCAGCUGUGUUACAGCAGACUUUCUUUGCAGUUAUUGGAGCCCUGUUACAGAGCAGUGGACCUGAGAGGACUGCACUUUUCAUCAGGGACUUCUUAAUUACUCAAAUGACUGGAAAAGAGCUCUUUGAGAUGUGGAAGAUAAUAAAUCCCAUGGGGCUAUUGGUAGAAGAACUGAAGAAAAGGAAUGUUUCAGCUCCUGAAUCAAGACUUACUAGGCAGUCUGGUGGCACCACAGCUUUGCCUUUGUAUUUUGUUGGCUUAUACUGUGAUAAAAAGUUGAUUGCAGAAGGACCUGGGGAAACAGUAUUGGUUGCAGAAGAAGAGGCUGCUCGAGUGGCCCUUAGAAAACUUUAUGGAUUCACAGAAAAUAGACGGCCGUGGAACUAUUCCAAGCCCAAAGAAACCUUGAGAGCAGAAAAGAGCAUCACUGCCAGCUAGCCGCCAUGGAUGCAGCAGCCUGAAACUUGAGAGCGAAAGUGAGAUAAAUGUCAAAGGUGUUUCAAGCCAGACAUUUUCACAAUUGUGAAGAAAUAGAUGUUUUGUUUCUGUUUUUUACUGUGUUCCCAAAAUUAAAUAAGUGUUAACCAAGUCACAGUGUUUUUGGUUUUGUUUUUCUGAAAUCUUGGUUUGAUCAAAUCUUUUUUUUUUUCUCUUGAGAUGGAGUCUUACUCUGUCGCCCAGGCUGGACUGCAGUGGUGCGAUCUCGGCUCACUGCAACCUCCACCUCACAGGUUCAAGCGAUUCUCGUGGCUCAGCCUCCCUAGUAGCUGGGAUUACAGGCACACACCACCAUACCUGGCUAAUUUUUGUAUUUUUGGUAGACAUGGGGUUUCACCAAGUUGGCUAGGCUAGUCUUGAACUCCUGACCUCAGGUGAUCCACCCGCCUUGGCCUCCCAAAGUGCUGGGAUUACAGGUGUGAGCCACUAUACCCGACCAGAUCAAAUCUUUUUUUGACAUUUUUGCAAAAAAAUUUUCCUAAUGUUCUUGAUUUAAUUGUAUAGAAUUUGUAUAAUUAGGUGUAUUUUAUUUGCGUCUAGCUUUGAGGUAUCAUAAUUUAUGUAUCUUAUGUGAAUUUUUUGCUGUAAUACCAAUAAAGUUUUUUUUCUCCACAUGUUAA